GCCAUUACUGCAGGAAAAGGUCCCGGAGAGCUGAGCAGUCAAGAUGUGUGACUUCACCGAAGACCAGACCGCAGAGUUCAAGGAGGCCUUCCAGCUGUUUGACCGAACAGGUGAUGGCAAGAUCCUGUACAGCCAGUGUGGGGAUGUGAUGAGGGCCCUGGGCCAGAACCCUACCAACGCCGAGGUGCUCAAGGUCCUGGGGAACCCCAAGAGUGAUGAGAUGAAUGUGAAGGUGCUGGACUUUGAGCACUUUCUGCCCAUGCUGCAGACAGUGGCCAAGAACAAGGACCAGGGCACCUAUGAGGAUUAUGUCGAAGGACUUCGGGUGUUUGACAAGGAAGGAAAUGGCACCGUCAUGGGUGCUGAAAUCCGGCAUGUUCUUGUCACACUGGGUGAGAAGAUGACAGAGGAAGAAGUAGAGAUGCUGGUGGCAGGGCAUGAGGACAGCAAUGGUUGUAUCAACUAUGAAGCGUUUGUGAGGCAUAUCCUGUCGGGGUGACGGGCCCAUGGGGCGGAGCUCGUCCGCAUGGUGCUGAAUGGCUGAGGACCUUCCCAGUCUCCCCAGAGUCCGUGCCUUUCCCUGUGUGAAUUUUGUAUCUAGCCUAAAGUUUCCCUAGGCUUUCUUGUCUCAGCAACUUUCCCAUCUUGUCUCUCUUGGAUGAUGUUUGCCGUCAGCAUUCACCAAAUAAACUUGCUCUCUGGGCCCUC